GUUUCCACGGACGCCCAGGAGACAGCCGGUUGCUGAGCCGGGAGCGCUGACUGGCCCGGCUGGGCAGGAAGGGAAACUGAAAGAAAGAGGGGAAGAGUAUUAAAGACCAUUUCUGGCUGGGCAGGGCACUCUCAGCAGCUCAACUGCCCAGCGUGACCAGUGGCCACCUCUGCAGUGUCUUCCACAACCUGGAUGUUCCUGAACUCCAAGUUGAAAAACCUCUGAAGUUCAACUCAAUUCUGAAAGUCAACAAAGAAAUAAAGGAGGAUGUCAAUAGUCUUGACUCGUCUGCUGAACAAAUCCUCUGACCUCAGGCCGGCUGUGAACGUAGUUCCUGAGAGAUAGCAAACAUGCCCAACAGUGAGCCCGCAUCUCUGCUGGAGCUGUUCAACAGCAUCGCCACACAAGGGGAGCUCGUAAGGUCCCUCAAAGCGGGAAAUGCGUCAAAGGAUGAAAUUGAUUCUGCAGUAAAGAUGUUGGUGUCAUUAAAAAUGAGCUACAAAGCUGCCGCGGGGGAGGAUUACAAGGCUGACUGUCCUCCAGGGAACCCAGCACCUACCAGUAAUCAUGGCCCAGAUGCCACAGAAGCUGAAGAGGAUUUUGUGGACCCAUGGACAGUACAGACAAGCAGUGCAAAAGGCAUAGACUACGAUAAGCUCAUUGUUCGGUUUGGAAGUAGUAAAAUUGACAAAGAGCUAAUAAACCGAAUAGAGAGAGCCACCGGCCAAAGACCACACCACUUCCUGCGCAGAGGCAUCUUCUUCUCACACAGAGAUAUGAAUCAGGUUCUUGAUGCCUAUGAAAAUAAGAAGCCAUUUUAUCUGUACACGGGCCGGGGCCCCUCUUCUGAAGCAAUGCAUGUAGGUCACCUCAUUCCAUUUAUUUUCACAAAGUGGCUCCAGGAUGUAUUUAACGUGCCCUUGGUCAUCCAGAUGACGGAUGACGAGAAGUAUCUGUGGAAGGACCUGACCCUGGACCAGGCCUAUAGCUAUGCUGUGGAGAAUGCCAAGGACAUCAUCGCCUGUGGCUUUGACAUCAACAAGACUUUCAUAUUCUCUGACCUGGACUACAUGGGGAUGAGCUCAGGUUUCUACAAAAAUGUGGUGAAGAUUCAAAAGCAUGUUACCUUCAACCAAGUGAAAGGCAUUUUCGGCUUCACUGACAGCGACUGCAUUGGGAAGAUCAGUUUUCCUGCCAUCCAGGCUGCUCCCUCCUUCAGCAACUCAUUCCCACAGAUCUUCCGAGACAGGACGGAUAUCCAGUGCCUUAUCCCAUGUGCCAUUGACCAGGAUCCUUACUUUAGAAUGACAAGGGACGUCGCCCCCAGGAUCGGCUAUCCUAAACCAGCCCUGCUGCACUCCACCUUCUUCCCAGCCCUGCAGGGCGCCCAGACCAAAAUGAGUGCCAGCGACCCCAACUCCUCCAUCUUCCUCACCGACACGGCCAAGCAGAUCAAAACCAAGGUCAAUAAGCAUGCGUUUUCUGGAGGGAGAGACACCAUCGAGGAGCACAGGCAGUUUGGGGGCAACUGUGAUGUGGACGUGUCUUUCAUGUACCUGACCUUCUUCCUCGAGGACGACGACAAGCUCGAGCAGAUCAGGAAGGAUUACACCAGCGGAGCCAUGCUCACCGGUGAGCUCAAGAAGGCACUCAUAGAGGUUCUGCAGCCCUUGAUCGCAGAGCACCAGGCCCGGCGCAAGGAGGUCACGGAUGAGAUAGUGAAAGAGUUCAUGACUCCCCGGAAGCUGUCCUUCGACUUUCAGUAGCACUCGUUUUACAUAUGCUUAUAAAAGAAGUGAUGUAUCAGUAAUGUAUCAAUAAUCCCAGCCCAGUCAAAGCACCGCCACCUGUAGGCUUCUGUCUCAUGGUAAUUACUGGGCCUGGCCUCUGUAAGCCUGUGUAUGUUAUCAAUACUGUUUCUUCCUGUGAGUUCCAUUAUUUCUAUCUCUUAUGGGCAAAGCAUUGUGGGUAAUUGGUGCUGGCUAACAUUGCAUGGUCGGAUAGAGAAGUCCAGCUGUGAGUCUCUCCCCAAAGCAGCCCCACAGUGGAGCCUUUGGCUGGAAGUCCAUGGGCCACCCUGUUCUUGUCCAUGGAGGACUCCGAGGGUUCCAAGUAUACUCUUAAGACCCACUCUGUUUAAAAAUAUAUAUUCUAUGUAUGCGUAUAUGGAAUUGAAAUGUCAUUAUUGUAACCUAGAAAGUGCUUUGAAAUAUUGAUGUGGGGAGGUUUAUUGAGCACAAGAUGUAUUUCAGCCCAUGCCCCCUCCCAAAAAGAAAUUGAUAAGUAAAAGCUUCGUUAUACAUUUGACUAAGAAAUCACCCAGCUUUAAAGCUGCUUUUAACAAUGAAGAUUGAACAGAGUUCAGCAAUUUUGAUUAAAUUAAGACUUGGGGGUGAAACUUUCCAGUUUACUGAACUCCAGACCAUGCAUGUAGUCCACUCCAGAAAUCAUGCUCGCUUCCCUUGGCACACCAGUGUUCUCCUGCCAAAUGACCCUAGACCCUCUGUCCUGCAGAGUCAGGGUGGCUUUUCCCCUGACUGUGUCCGAUGCCAAGGAGUCCUGGCCUCCGCAGAUGCUUCAUUUUGACCCUUGGCUGCAGUGGAAGUCAGCACAGAGCAGUGCCCUGGCUGUGUCCCUGGACGGGUGGACUUAGCUAGGGAGAAAGUCGAGGCAGCAGCCCUCGAGGCCCUCACAGAUGUCUAGGCAGGCCUCAUUUCAUCACGCAGCAUGUGCAGGCCUGGAAGAGCAAAGCCAAAUCUCAGGGAAGUCCUUGGUUGAUGUAUCUGGGUCUCCUCUGGAGCACUCUGCCCUCCUGUCACCCAGUAGAGUAAAUAAACUUCCUUGGCUCCUG